CUUUAAGCACUUGGAAGGGCUUGGGUAGCCUGCUGGGAAGGAAGGACCCCAAAGUACCUCAAAGGUGCGGAGAAAUGUUCAUCGGUCCAGUCCACAGAAAUGCUUGUUUGGCUCCCCAACGAUUGGUGAGUUGUCUGUGUAUUCUCCGGGGUAACUAUGGGUCACGCAGAGUCUAAACAUUAUGCUUAUCUCUGCUAUAUUAAAUUCCUGUUAAAAUGGGGGAGUUCGGGUUCCCAUGGAAAAUAUGGUCACCCUAUUCAGGGCAGUGGAAGAACACUGUCCUUGGUUUCCUGAAAAGGGAACGUUAGAUGUGGAACUAUGGGAUCAUGUUGGUGCAAAAUUCCGAGAACUGGUCCCAACAGGAAAUUAUGUUCCUGUCACUGUUUGGGGUGAUUGGGCCUUGGUACGUGCCAUCCUAAUGACAUACCAAUCCCGUGACACCCUGCAGUUACCACAGUUUUCUGAAUCUGGCCACCCUCUACCUCUUCCUCAGCUUUCCUCUCCCACUCGGCCUUCAUUAUCUGCUCAGCCCCUCCCUUUGCCUACUCCUCCCCCACCUGACGAUACUGAGGAUUCAAUAUCUAACUCCAGUGACUUUGGCUUAACAUCACCCCCUGAUGAUCUUAUUUCUUUUCACGAAGAGCCGACACUUGUAGCUCCUGCGGCCCCAACUCAGACAGCCCAGGACCAUAUCUAUGCUAACUCUUCCCUCUCCAAACCUUUACAGUCUUUGCCUCCGGAGCCAUCCAAACUACAAUUUACCUGUAAUUCUGCAGGCCCUCCCCCAUCCACCACAGCCCCUCACCCUCCUAUCAUUUUGGUCCCUCAACCGGUCACUUUGCCAUCCACUCAACCUGCUUCUCUGUACCCUUCUUCAUGCAGGGACACCCCUGCCACUCUGGUUGUGCAGGACUGGGCCAGUAAUCACCAGUAUGCUUCUGCCUCUUCUGCUCCCCCAAUGCCCCUUUCUCACACUCUUAUACCAGUCCGACCCCGUCAAUCUCAGUUUCUCUUAUCUAUACAUACUUUUCCUGUCACUUCUAUGCCGACUCUAUCUCAUGUGCCUGCUCUUGAAACUUUCAUGCAAUGCUUAUUACGCCAAAACAAACAAGUAGAUUAGAGGCGUGGGCUUAUUCGGUCAUGCUGGAACCUCCUAAUGCUCAAGGGGUACAAGUGUGUCGAUAUACGCCGCUCAAUCUUACCUUUUUAAAAGAAUUCAAGGAUGCUUGUACUCAGUAUGUUCCUACUUCUCCAUAUGUUAAAACGGUAUUACAGACUCUUUGUACCGAGGUCAUUUUGCUUCCUAUAGACUGCGACCUUUUGGCAAAAGCUGUUCUAACUCCAUCUCAGCAUUUACAAUUCCAUACCUGGUGGUCAGAGGAGGCCCGCCUGCAGGCUCAGCUAAAUCGGGCUGAUGGCAUUCCAAUUACUCAGGCUCAGCUCACAGGCUCCGAUAAUUACUCUGAUACUACUGCUCAUUUAGGCUUUGAUGCUCUCACCACGGAACAAGUAACAAAGGUGUGUAUGAGAGCUUGGGAUAAAUUACGCACCCCAGGCCAAGCUUCUGUUUCUUUUACUAUUGUUAAACAGGGUCACAAUGAAUUAUAUCUUGAUUUUUUAGCUAAAUUACAAGAUGCUGUUGAAAAAUCUGUCUCUGAUGAGCACACUCAAGGUAUUCUUCUUCAUAUGUUAGCUUUUCAAAAUGCGAACCAUGAGUGUAAAAUGGCCGUGCAUUCCAUCCUACGUCAAAAUUUACCUGAUCAUGAGGUGUUGCCUGCAUAUAUUAAAGCUUGUGAAGGCGUUGGAUCGGAGACCCACAGAGCUAUUCUGUGGGCACCGGCCAUGAAGCACGGCAACCAAACUGGCUCGACUGAUUCUUUUCUUGGAGCCUGCUAUAAUUGUGGCCAACUUGGUCAUACCCAAAAAAACUACACUGUUAAAAACUUAAAAGCGGCCAAGCCGGCUCAACAAACACGGCCAAAUGCUCCUGCUACUGUUUGCCUGCGUUGUCGUAAGGGUAAACAUUGGGCAAGUACUUGCCACUCAGUCUGAUAUAGAUGAAAAUCCCUUGCCACAGAACCAGGGAAACAGGAAGCAAGGCCAGUCCCAGGCCCCAAUAUCAAAUGGGACACCUCGGACUCAGACCAAUGUUGUGUUUUUGCGUCAAGCAGUCCCAACGCAGCCCCCAGCACAAACAAAUUUACCUACAGCCAAU